AUGAGUUUGUUCCUGCCCGCAGAAGCCGCCUCGCCUCCGCAGUGCCACCUCUGCUGCCCCCAGCCACCGGCACAGCUGAGUCAAGUAUGUCCUGAUCCAAUCCGUGCCCUGCACUGCUGCUUCUCCCUACCACCAUUUCUCUCCGUGUGCAAGGACAGGAGGCCACUCCAGCUUUCCCCUGUGAGGAAUUUUAGUAAACGUUCUCAGGGACACCAGUCCACGGGGUCCGGAUCCAAGUGCACUGUUAUCCUCAAAUCCAGUCCACAGGGUCCAGAUCCGAGUGCGCUGUUAUCCUCAAAUCCAGUCCACGGGGUCCGGAUCCGAGUGCGCUGUUAUCCCCAAACACUGUUGCAAUCCCUUUCCUGGUUGAAGUCAGGUGGACUCUGUUAUACUAAGAAGUCUCUGUGUUUGUGCUGCUUUGGAAACGCCUUAGUUCAUCCUAGCUUGGCCUCCCUGAGAGCAUCGUCUGCACCAUCCUCUCUGCAGACCCCUCCUAUUUCCCUGCAAAGCCCCUCCUCGCGAAUUAAAAAGAAAAAACAAAAACAAAAAACAAAUGAAGAAGCAACUGGUACGAGCAGAUUUGGUGCAAGAGAACCAAUCGCAGGAGCCGCCCAAGCUCACUUAGGAAAAGAGCUGAGCGACAGCAGCUGCACCCAGAAGGUGGAGACCGCAUGCGAACCCAGGAUCCCAGGCAGCACAAGGCUAGAGACCCUGCAAGCAGCCAUGGCUGUGCGUUCAUGCAGAGCGUCAUCACAGCCAACACGGUCUUCCUCCUGGUUAACCAAGAUCCCGUUUCAGCCAUUCUGGAAUUGCAGGGCUGGCCAGAACUUUAGGAACAAUACAUGCAAUGCCUUCAUUUUACACCCCAUUGAGAGUCCAGCACAGCCAGGUCCCAGAGGAGCGGCUUCUUCCCAGCACAGCCAGGUCCCAAAGGAGCAGCUUCUUCCUGAGUCCUGCAUAGACAGGUCCCUGAGGAGCAGCUUCUUUCUGAGUCCUGCAUGUCACUUGUCUUGCGAUUCCUGCGUUGGAGGCCAUGUCAUUGAUGCGACUCCACUCCCAGCCCUGAGCCUUGCAAAAACCUUAUUUAAUGCCUUGGAGCUGAGUGGAUGGCGACACCAGCUACAUGACAACCAAGGACCAGGCAUCCAGGAUCCGAGUGUGUGCUGUAAUCAAAGAAAACUUAAUCCACCACAUAUUAGUGACAUGCACAACAGUCAUUCUGCACAUGGUCAUUAGCCAUCAACGGUAAGCAGCUCUGGUAAACGGCGGUAACUGGUAUGCUACUACAAAGCCGAAUGCCUUGCCCCCACUUUCUGUCUUUAUUUUAUUGAUCCCAAUGAAUGGCAUCGACGUCAACAGUUCCCUUAACUUUUCCACAAUGGAGUCCUCAUCUCAAUGCCCCUCCCCUCAUCCGCCCCAUCCCUGCUUCUUUCUCUCUUCAUCUCUCUUUGCAUUGUGCACACACACGUGCACCCUCACACACAUGCACACAUACACGUAUGUGCACACAUACAUACGUGCACACACACGCACAGACAGCUGAAGAUUCCCGUGAUGGCCCAUUUGCUCAGUGUUGCCCCACACAGCAUCUGCCAACACUGUGCUUUAGUGGACGGCGGUAUUUAUGGCGCCUUACACAGUAUUGUCAGAUGCAGGACUGACCUUGUUCUGGAGGACAACUGAGGCAACCUCUGCUGUCUCCCCUGGCUGCCACCGCCAUGCCAUGGCAUCAACACCCCAGGAAGGAAAGCUCCUGCUGCCUGCAGUCCAGAGGAUGCUUGGGAUUCCUGGUGGUAAACAUGCUGAGCUUCCCCGCUCAUCCUCCCACUAACGGCCAACAGUCUGGGCUUUCCUUUUCUUUGUUCUGUCUCCCAGGUCUAUGACCUUGCCUUUGAGAAUGCAAAGUGACCAUAAAUAGUAGGGCUCCUGAAAGAUUAAAGAAGGCAAACUUCUGAAUAUUUUGUAAUUACAGAUAGAUAAAUAGAUAGAUAGAUAAAUAGAUAGAUAGAUAGAUAGAUAGAUAGAUGACAGAUAGAGAGGCAGAGAGAUGCAUGUAUGUGAUAUGCCUCCUACCUUAACCAUCUC